CUCCUCACUGUCGCUGCCGAGAUCCACAGUCGGUUGUGGCUCAGCCCCUGUUGCAGGGGACAAGUGAGGGAGACUUCCCUGUCCUGCCCUGAGACGCCGCCCUCCCGGGGUUGGGGACAGAGCAGGUGCAGAGGCACUGCAGCUGCUCGGUUGCCCAGCCUCCUGAAUGAUGCCAGCCCAGUAUGCUCUAACCUCCAGCCUGGUUCUCCUGGUGCUGCUGAGCACAGCCAGAGCAGGCCCCUUCUCUUCACGGUCCAAUGUGACACUGCCAGCCCCCCGGCCCCCUCCCCAGCCAGGGGGCCACACAGUGGGGGCUGGAGUGGGAAGCCCCUCUUCUCAGCUUUACGAGCACACAGUGGAAGGAGGGGAGAAGCAGGUGGUAUUCACCCACCGCAUUAACCUGCCCCCUUCCACUGGCUGUGGCUGUCCCCCAGGCACCGAGCCCCCAGUCCUUGCUUCAGAGGUACAGGCCCUGAGGGUCCGUCUAGAGAUCCUGGAGGAGUUGGUGAAGGGGCUCAAGGAACAGUGCACUGGGGGAUGUUGUCCUGCCUCUGCCCAAGCUGGCACAGGUCAGACAGAUGUGCGGACCCUCUGCAGUCUCCAUGGUGUGUUUGAUCUGAGCCGCUGCACCUGUUCCUGUGAGCCAGGCUGGGGUGGGCCCACCUGCUCAGACCCCACAGAUGCUGAGAUCCCUCCCUCUUCCCCACCCUCAGCCUCGGGGUCCUGCCCAGAUGACUGCAAUGAUCAGGGUCGCUGUGUCCGUGGUCGUUGCGUGUGCUUUCCCGGCUACACUGGCCCCAGCUGUGGCUGGCCAUCCUGUCCCGGGGACUGCCAAGGCCGUGGGCGCUGCGUGCAGGGCGUGUGUGUGUGCCGGGCAGGCUUCUCAGGCCCCGACUGCAGCCAGCGCUCCUGCCCUCGAGGUUGCAGCCAGAGGGGACGCUGUGAGGGUGGGCGCUGCGUGUGUGACCCAGGCUACACUGGUGACGACUGUGGCAUGAGGAGCUGCCCUCGCGGUUGCAGUCAGAGGGGGCGCUGUGAGAAUGGGCGCUGCGUGUGUAACCCCGGCUACACUGGCGAGGACUGUGGGGUGAGGAGCUGCCCUCGGGGCUGCAGCCAGCGGGGACGCUGCAAGGACGGGCGCUGCGUGUGUGACCCCGGCUACACUGGCGAGGACUGUGGUACGCGGAGCUGCCCCUGGGACUGUGGCGAGGGCGGGCGCUGCGUGGACGGCCGCUGCGUGUGCUGGCCCGGGUACACAGGCGAGGACUGCAGCACGCGGACAUGUCCGAGGGACUGCCGGGGCCGCGGGCGCUGCGAGGACGGCGAAUGCAUUUGCGACACGGGCUACAGCGGGGACGACUGCGGCGUGCGCAGCUGCCCUGGCGACUGCAACCAAAGGGGCCGCUGCGAGGACGGCCGCUGCGUGUGCUGGCCGGGGUACACUGGAACCGAUUGCGGCUCGCGCGCCUGCCCACGCGACUGUAGAGGUCGCGGGCGCUGCGAGAACGGCGUGUGUGUUUGCAAUGCGGGCUACAGCGGCGAGGACUGCGGUGUGCGCAGCUGUCCUGGGGACUGUCGUGGCCGGGGCCGCUGUGAGAGUGGCCGCUGCAUGUGUUGGCCGGGGUACACAGGCCGGGACUGCGGCACGCGCGCCUGUCCUGGCGACUGUCGCGGGCGCGGGCGCUGCGUGGAUGGCCGCUGCGUGUGCAACCCGGGCUUCACCGGUGAGGACUGUGGGAGCCGUCGCUGUCCCGGGGACUGCCGUGGGCACGGCCUUUGCGAGGAUGGCGUGUGCGUGUGUGACGCAGGCUACUCAGGGGAAGACUGCAGCACGCGCAGCUGCCCCGGGGGCUGCCGAGGCCGCGGCCAGUGCCUAGAUGGGCGGUGUGUGUGCGAGGACGGCUACUCUGGCGAGGAUUGCGGUGUGAGGCAGUGCCCGAAUGACUGCAGCCAGCACGGCGUGUGCCAGGACGGUGUGUGCAUCUGUUGGGAAGGCUACGUGAGUGAGGACUGCAGCAUCCGCACCUGCCCCUCCAACUGCCACGGGAGGGGCCGCUGUGAGGAAGGGCGCUGCCUGUGCGACCCAGGCUACACCGGCCCUACCUGUGCCACCCGCAUGUGCCCGGCUGACUGCCGGGGACGUGGGCGGUGUGUGCAAGGAGUGUGCCUGUGCCACGUGGGCUAUGGCGGUGAGGACUGCGGGCAGGAAGAGCCUCCAGCCAGCGCCUGCCCUGGAGGCUGCGGGCCCCGGGAACUGUGCCGGGCAGGCCAGUGUGUGUGUGUAGAGGGCUUCCGAGGCCCUGACUGUGCCAUCCAGACAUGCCCAGGGGACUGCCGUGGCCGAGGAGAGUGUCACGAUGGCAGCUGUGUCUGCAAAGAUGGGUAUGCUGGCGAAGACUGCGGAGAAGAGGUGCCAACCAUUGAGGGCAUGAGGAUGCAUCUCUUGGAGGAGACAACAGUUCGGACAGAGUGGACCCCGGCUCCUGGCCCCGUGGAUGCCUAUGAAAUUCAGUUCAUCCCCACGACAGAGGGGGCGAGCCCCCCAUUCACAGCACGGGUUCCAAGCUCUGCCUCAGCCUAUGACCAGAGAGGACUGGCCCCUGGACAGGAGUACCAGGUCACUGUCCGAGCCCUUCGAGGGACCAGCUGGGGCCUUCCUGCCUCCAAGACCAUCACCACCAUGAUCGAUGGGCCCCAGGACCUCCGAGUGGUGGCUGUGACACCGACAACACUGGAGCUUGGCUGGCUGCGUCCCCAGGCUGAGGUGGACCGAUUUGUGGUGUCCUACGUCAGUGCCGGCAACCAGAGGGUGAGGCUGGAAGUGCCCCCUGAAGCAGACGGGACGCUGCUGACUGACCUGAUGCCAGGCGUAGAAUAUGUGGUGACUGUCACAGCGGAGCGGGGCCGGGCAGUCAGCUACCCAGCUUCUGUCAGGGCCAACACAGGGUCCUCACCCUUGGGCCUCUUGGGGACUACCGAUGAGCCUCCUCCCUCAGGCCCCUCGACGACGCAAGGGGCCCAGGCUCCUCUCCUGCAGCAGCGCCCCCAGGAGCUGGGAGAGUUGAGGGUGCUGGGCAGAGAUGAGACAGGGCGCCUCCGUGUGGUCUGGACCGCCCAGCCUGACACCUUUGCCUACUUCCAACUGCGCAUGCGGGUGCCCGAGGGGCCGGGGGCACAUGAGGAAGUGCUGCCAGGGGACGUCCGCCAGGCUCUGGUGCCUCCACCCCCUCCUGGAACCCCGUAUGAGCUGUCACUUCAUGGGGUCCCUCCUGGGGGCAAGCCCUCUGACCCCAUCAUCUACCAAGGCAUUAUGGACAAGGAUGAGGAGAAGCCUGGGAAGUCCUCAGGCCCACCACGCCUGGGUGAGCUGACGGUGACAGACAGGACCUCCGACUCCUUGCUCCUGCGCUGGACGGUCCCCGAGGGCGAGUUUGACUCCUUCGUGAUCCAGUACAAAGACAGGGACGGGCAGCCCCAGGUGGUGCCCGUGGAAGGACCCCAGCGCUCGGCCGUCAUCACCUCCCUGGAUCCUGGCCGCAAGUACAAAUUUGUCCUGUAUGGGUUUGUUGGCAAGAAGAGGCAUGGUCCGCUGGUGGCUGAAGCCAAGAUCUUGCCUCAGAGUGACCCAAGUCCAGGGACUCCACCCCACCUGGGAAACCUGUGGGUGACAGACCCUACCCCAGAUUCACUGCACCUCUCCUGGACUGUCCCUGAGGGCCAGUUUGACACCUUCAUGGUCCAGUACAGGGACAGGGAUGGACGGCCCCAGGUGGUACCUGUGGAAGGGCCCGAGCGUUCAUUUGUUGUCUCCUCACUGGACCCUGACCACAAGUACAGAUUCACUCUGUUUGGAAUUGCGAACAAGAAGCGGUAUGGCCCCCUCACGGCCGAUGGCACCACUGCUCCAGAGAGGAAAGAGGAGCCCCCCCGCCCUGAGUUCCUGGAGCAGCCCCUCCUGGGGGAACUGACAGUGACCGGCGUGACCCCAGACUCCUUGCGUCUCUCAUGGACAGUGGCCCAGGGCCCCUUCGACUCAUUCAUGGUCCAGUACAAGGAUGCACAGGGGCAGCCCCAGGCAGUGCCUGUUGCGGGGGAUGAGAAUGAGGUUACUGUCCCCGGCCUGGAUCCCGACCGGAAGUAUAAGAUGAACCUCUACGGGCUUCGUGGCAGGCAGCGUGUGGGGCCCGAGUCUGUGGUGGCCAAGACUGCUCCUCAGGAGGAUGUGGACGAGACCCCCAGCCCCACAGAACUGGGCACGGAGGCCCCGGAGUCCCCCGAGGAGCCGCUCCUGGGGGAGCUGACAGUGACAGGAUCCUCCCCUGAUUCGCUGAGCCUCUUCUGGACCGUCCCCCAGGGCAGCUUCGACUCUUUCACCGUGCAGUACAAGGACAGGGAUGGGCGGCCCCGGGCGGUGCGUGUUGGGGGCAAGGAGAGUGAGGUCACCGUGGGAGGCCUAGAGCCCGGGCACAAGUACAAGAUGCACCUGUACGGCCUCCACGAGGGGCAGCGCGUGGGCCCGGUGUCCGCCGUGGGCGUGACAGCCCCACAACAAGAAGAGACCCCUCCAGCCACUGAGUCCCCGCUGGAGCCACGCCUAGGAGAGCUGACAGUGACAGAUGUGACCCCCAACUCUGUGGGCCUCUCCUGGACAGUCCCCGAGGGCCAGUUUGACUCCUUCAUAGUCCAGUACAAGGACAAGGACGGGCAGCCCCAGGUGGUGCCGGUGGCGGCAGACCAGCGAGAGGUCACAGUCUACAACCUGGAGCCUGAGAGAAAAUAUAAGAUGAACAUGUAUGGACUACAUGAUGGGCAACGCAUGGGCCCCCUGUCUGUGGUCAUCGUGACGGCUCCCCUCCCACCAGCCCCAGCCACAGAGGCCUCCAAGCCUCCCCUGGAGCCACGCCUAGGGGAGCUGACAGUGACGGAUAUAACCCCUGACUCUGUGGGCCUCUCAUGGACAGUCCCUGAGGGUGAAUUCGACUCCUUUGUGGUUCAGUACAAGGACAGGGACGGGCAGCCCCAGGUGGUGCCCGUGGCUGCAGAUCAGCGGGAGGUCACUAUCCCUGACCUGGAACCCUCCCGCAAGUACAAGUUCCUGCUCUUUGGGAUCCAGGAUGGGAAACGACGCAGCCCAGUCUCUGUGGAGGCAAAGACGGUUGCCCGAGGUGACGCCAGCCCAGGGGCCCCACCCCGCCUUGGGGAGCUGUGGGUGACAGACCCCACCCCAGACUCACUGCGCCUCUCCUGGACGGUUCCUGAGGGCCAGUUCGACUCUUUUGUGGUCCAGUUCAAGGACAAAGACGGGCCCCAGGUGGUGCCCGUGGAGGGCCAUGAGCGCUCUGUCACUGUCACCCCUCUGGAUGCCGGCCGCAAGUACAGAUUCCUCCUCUAUGGCCUCCUGGGCAAGAAGCGCCAUGGCCCUCUCACUGCCGACGGCACCACGGAAGCCCGGAGUGCUAUGGAUGAUACUGGAACAAAGCGUCCCCCAAAACCCCGUCUGGGGGAGGAGCUGCAGGUGACCACCGUGACCCAGAACUCCGUGGGCCUCUCCUGGACAGUCCCUGAGGGCCAGUUUGACUCCUUUGUGGUCCAGUACAAAGACAGGGACGGGCAGCCCCAGGUGGUGCCCGUGGAGGGCAGCCUCAGGGAGGUCAGCGUGCCGGGCCUGGACCCUGCCCACAGGUACAAGCUGCUGCUCUACGGGCUGCACCACGGCAAGCGUGUGGGCCCCAUCUCGGCCGUCGCCAUUACUGCCGGCAGGGAAGAAACGGAAACUGAGACCACGGCCCCGACCCCUCCAGCGCCUGAGCCCCACCUCGGGGAGUUGACAGUGGAGGAGGCCACGUCACACACCCUGCAUCUCUCCUGGAUGGUGACUGAGGGAGAAUUUGACUCCUUCGAAAUCCAGUACACAGAUAGAGACGGGCAACUCCAAAUGGUCCGCAUAGGAGGUGACCGGAAUGACAUCACCCUCUCUGGCCUGGAAUCCGACCACAGAUACCUGGUGACCCUGUAUGGUUUCAGUGAUGGGAAGCAUGUAGGUCCUGUCCAUGUCGAGGCCCUGACAGUCCCGGAGGAGGAGAAGCCUUCAGAACCUCCCACCGCAACCCCCGAGCCCCCCAUCAAGCCUCGCCUGGGGGAGCUGACCGUGACAGAUGCCACCCCUGACUCCCUCAGCCUGUCCUGGACAGUUCCCGAGGGACAGUUUGACCACUUCCUGGUCCAGUACAGGAAUGGAGAUGGGCAGCCCAAGGCAGUGAGGGUGCCAGGGCACGAGGAAGGGGUCACCAUCUCGGGCCUGGAGCCAGACCAUAAAUACAAGAUGAACCUGUACGGCUUCCACGGUGGCCAGCGCAUGGGCCCUGUGUCUGUCGUCGGGGUGACAGCUGCAGAGGAAGAGACCCCCAGCCCCACAGAACCCAGCAUGGAGGCCCCGGAGCCCGCUGAGGAGCCGCUCCUGGGGGAGCUAACAGUGACAGGAUCCUCCCCUGACUCGCUGAGCCUCUCCUGGACCGUCCCCCAGGGCCGCUUCGACUCCUUCACCGUGCAGUACAAGGACAGGGACGGGCGGCCCCAGGUGGUGCGUGUUGGGGGCGAGGAGAGUGAAGUCACCGUGGGGGGCCUGGAGCCUGGGCGCAAGUACAAGAUGCACCUGUACGGCCUCCACGAGGGGCGGCGCGUGGGCCCAGUGUCUGCUGUGGGCGUCACGGCCCCCGAAGAGGAGUCCCCUGAUGCUCCUCUUGCAAAGCUGCGCCUAGGGCAGAUGACAGUGAGAGACAUCACCUCCGACUCCCUCAGCCUCUCCUGGACAGUCCCCGAGGGCCAGUUUGACCAUUUCUUGGUCCAGUUUAAGAAUGGGGACGGGCAGCCCAAGGCGGUGCGGGUGCCGGGACACGAGGAUGGGGUCACCAUCUCGGGCCUGGAGCCAGACCACAAGUACAAGAUGAACCUGUACGGCUUCCACGGUGGCCAGCGCGUGGGCCCCGUGUCUGCUGUUGGUUUAACUGCCCCAGGAAAGGAUGAAGAAAUGGCCCCAGCCUCGACAGAACCUCCCACCCCUGAACCCCCCAUCAAGCCUCGCCUGGAGGAGCUGACCGUGACAGAUGCGACCCCUGACUCCCUCAGCCUGUCCUGGACGGUUCCCGAGGGACAGUUUGACCACUUCCUGGUCCAGUACAAGAAUGGGGAUGGGCAGCCCAAGGCAACACGGGUGCCAGGACAUGAGGACAGGGUCACCAUCUCCGGCCUGGAGCCAGACAACAAGUACAAGAUGAACCUGUACGGCUUCCACGGUGGCCAGCGUGUGGGCCCCGUGUCUGCCAUCGGGGUGACAGCUGCAGAGGAAGAGACCCCCAGCCCCACAGAACCCAGCAUGGAGGCCCCGGAGCCCCCUGAGGAGCCGCUCCUGGGGGAGCUAACAGUGACAGGAUCCUCCCCUGACUCGCUGAGCCUCUCCUGGACCGUCCCCCAGGGCCGCUUCGACUCCUUCACCGUGCAGUACAAGGACAGGGACGGGCGGCCCCAGGUGGUGCGUGUUGGGGGCGAGGAGAGCGAGGUCACCGUGGGGGGCCUGGAGCCUGGGCGCAAAUACAAGAUGCACCUGUAUGGCCUCCACGAGGGGCGGCGCGUGGGCCCGGUGUCCACCGUGGGCGUGACUGCCCCACAAGAGGAUGUGGACGAGACCCCCAGCCCUACAGAACCAGGCACAGAGGCCCCAGGGCCCCCCGAGGAGCCUCUCCUGGGGGAGCUGACAGUGACAGGAUCCUCCCCUGACUCGCUGAGCCUUUCCUGGACCGUCCCCCAGGGCCGCUUUGACUCCUUCACCGUGCAGUACAAGGACAGGGACGGGCGGCCCCAGGCGGUGCGUGUUGGGGGCCAGGAGAGCAAGGUCACUGUGAGGGGCCUGGAGCCUGGGCGCAAGUACAAGAUGCACCUGUACGGCCUCCACGAGGGGCGGCGCCUGGGCCCGGUGUCUGCCGUGGGCGUCACAGAGGAUGAAGCCGAGACCACCCAAGCAGUGCCUACCAUGACCCCUGAGCCCCCCAUCAAGCCUCGCCUGGGGGAGCUGACCAUGACAGAUGCCACCCCUGACUCCCUCAGCCUGUCCUGGACGGUUCCCGAGGGCCAGUUUGACCACUUCCUGGUCCAGUACAGGAAUGGGGAUGGGCAGCCCAAGGCGGUGCGGGUGCCGGGGCACGAGGACGGGGUCACCAUCUCAGGCCUGGAGCCAGACCAUAAAUACAAGAUGAACCUGUACGGCUUCCACGGUGGCCAGCGCGUGGGCCCCAUCUCUGUCAUUGGGGUGACGGCUGCAGAGGAAGAGACCCCCAGCCCCACGGAACUCAGCACUGAGGCCCCGGAGCCCCCUGAGGAGCCGCUCCUGGGGGAGCUGACAGUGACAGGAUCCUCCCCUGACUCGCUGAGCCUCUCCUGGACCAUCCCCCAGGGCCACUUCGACUCCUUCACCGUGCAGUACAAGGACAGGGACGGGCGGCCCCAGGUGAUGCGUGUCAGGGGCGAGGAGAGCGAGGUCACCGUGGGGGGCCUGGAGCCCGGGCGCAAAUACAAGAUGCACCUGUACGGCCUCCACGAGGGGCGGCGUGUGGGCCCGGUGUCCACCGUGGGUGUGACAGCUCCAGAGGAUGAAGCAGAGACCACCCAAGCAGUGCCCACCACAACCCCUGAGCCCCCCAACAAGCCUCGCCUCGGGGAGCUGACCGUGACAGAUGCCACCCCUGACUCCCUCAGCCUGUCCUGGAUGGUCCCCGAGGGCCAGUUUGACCACUUCCUGGUCCAGUACAGGAAUGGGGAUGGGCAGCCCAAGGUGGUGCGGGUGCCGGGGCACGAGGACGGGGUCACCAUCUCAGGCCUGGAGCCAGACCACAAGUACAAGAUGAACCUGUACGGCUUCCACGGUGGCCAGCGCGUGGGCCCCAUCUCUGUCAUUGGGGUGACAGCUGCAGAGGAAGAAACUCCCGCCCCCACAGAACCCAGCACGGAGGCCCCGGAGCCCCCUGAGGAGCCGCUCCUGGGGGAGCUGACAGUGACAGGAUCCUCCCCUGACUCGCUGAGCCUCUCCUGGACCAUCCCCCAGGGCCGCUUCGACUCCUUCACUGUGCAGUACAAGGACAGGGACGGGCGGCCCCAGGUGGUGCGUGUCAGGGGCGAGGAGAGCGAGGUCACCGUGGGGGGCCUGGAGCCCGGGUGCAAAUACAAGAUGCACCUGUACGGCCUCCACGAGGGGCAGCGCGUGGGCCCAGUGUCCGCUGUGGGUGUGACAGCUCCAAAGGAUGAAGCCGAGACCACCCAAGCAGUGCCUACCAUGACCCCUGAGCCCCCCAUCAAGCCUCGCCUGGGGGAGCUGACCGUGACAGAUGCCACCCCCGACUCCCUCAGCCUGUCCUGGAUGGUUCCCGAGGGCCAGUUUGACCACUUCCUGGUCCAGUACAGGAAUGGGGAUGGGCAGCCCAAGGCGGUGCGGGUGCCGGGGCACGAGGACGGGGUCACCAUCUCAGGCCUGGAGCCAGACCAUAAAUACAAGAUGAACCUGUACGGCUUCCACGGUGGCCAGCGCGUAGGCCCUGUGUCUGCCAUUGGGGUGACGGAGGAAGAGACCCCCAGCCCCACAGAACCCAGCACUGAGGCCCCGGAGGCCCCUGAGGAGCCGCUCCUGGGGGAGUUGACAGUGACAGGAUCCUCCCCUGACUCGCUGAGCCUCUCCUGGACCGUCCCCCAGGGCCGCUUCGACUCCUUCACCGUGCAGUACAAGGACAGGGACGGGCAGCCCCAGGUGGUGCGUGUCAGGGGCGAGGAGAGCGAGGUCACCGUGGGGGGCCUGGAGCCCGGGCGCAAAUACAAGAUGCAUCUGUACGGCCUCCACGAGGGGCAGCGCGUGGGCCCAGUGUCCACCGUGGGCAUCACGGCGCCCCUGCCCACACCACUGCCGGUGGAGCCCCGCCUGGGGGAGCUGGCGGUGGCGGCCGUGACCUCGGACUCAGUGGGCCUCUCAUGGACGGUGGCCCAGGGCCCCUUUGACUCCUUCCUGGUACAGUACAGGGACGCGCAGGGGCAGCCCCAGGCAGUGCCUGUGAGCGGAGACCUCCGAGCGGUCGCCGUCUCGGGGCUGGACCCGGCCCGCAAGUACAAGUUCCUGCUCUUUGGACUCCAGAAUGGGAAACGCCACGGCCCAGUCCCUGUGGAGGCCAGGACCGCCCCAGACACCAAACCGUCUCCCCGCCUGGGGGAGCUGACUGUGACAGAUGCGACCCCUGACUCCGUGGGCCUCUCGUGGACGGUCCCUGAGGGCGAAUUCGACUCCUUCGUGGUCCAGUACAAGGAUAAGGAUGGUCGGCUCCAGGUGGUGCCGGUGGCAGCCAACCAGCGGGAGGUCACAGUCCAGGGCCUGGAGCCCAGUAGGAAAUACAGGUUCCUGCUCUAUGGUCUGUCAGGCAGGAAACGACUGGGCCCCAUCUCUGCUGACAGCACCACAGCUCCCCUGGAGAAGGAGCUACCUCCCCACCUGGGGGAACUGACCGUGGCUGAGGAGACCUCCAGCUCUCUGCGCCUGUCCUGGACGGUAGCCCAGGGCCCCUUUGACUCCUUCGUGGUCCAGUACAGGGACACGGACGGGCAGCCCAGGGCAGUGCCUGUGGCCGCAGACCAGCGCACAGUCACCGUAGAGGACCUGGAGCCUGGCAAGAAAUACAAGUUUCUGCUCUACGGGCUCCUUGGGGGAAAGCGCCUGGGCCCGGUCUCUGCCCUGGGAAUGACAGCCCCAGAAGAGGACACACCAGCCCCAGAGUUAGCCCCAGAGGCCCCUGAGCCUCCUGAAGAGCCCCGCCUAGGAGUGCUGACCGUGACCGACACAACCCCAGACUCCAUGCGCCUCUCGUGGAGCGUGGCCCAGGGCCCCUUUGAUUCCUUCGUGGUCCAGUAUGAGGACACGAACGGGCAGCCCCAGGCCUUGCUCGUGGACGGCGACCAGAGCAAGAUCCUCAUCUCAGGCCUGGAGCCCAGCACCCCCUACAGGUUCCUCCUCUAUGGCCUCCAUGAAGGGAAGCGCCUGGGGCCCCUCUCAGCUGAGGGCACCACAGGGCUGGCUCCUGCUGGUCAGACCUCAGAGGAGUCAAGGCCCCGCCUGUCCCAGCUGUCUGUGACUGACGUGACCACCAGUUCACUGAGGCUCAACUGGGAGGCCCCACCGGGGGCCUUCGACUCCUUCCUGCUCCGCUUUGGGGUUCCAUCACCAAGCACUCUGGAGCCGCAUCCGCGUCCACUGCUGCAGCGCGAGCUGAUGGUGCCGGGGACGCGGCACUCGGCCGUGCUCCGGGACCUGCGUUCCGGGACUCUGUACAGCCUGACACUGUAUGGGCUGCGAGGACCCCACAAGGCCGACAGCAUCCAGGGAACCGCCCGCACCCUCAGCCCAGUUCUGGAGAGCCCCCGUGACCUCCAAUUCAGUGAAAUCAGGGAGACCUCAGCCAAGGUCAACUGGAUGCCCCCACCAUCCCGGGCGGACAGCUUCAAAGUCUCCUACCAGCUGGCGGACGGAGGGGAGCCUCAGAGUGUGCAGGUGGAUGGCCAGGCCCGGACCCAGAAACUCCAGGGGCUGAUCCCAGGCGCUCGCUAUGAGGUGACCGUGGUCUCGGUCCGAGGCUUUGAGGAGAGUGAGCCUCUCACAGGCUUCCUCACCACGGUUCCUGACGGUCCCACACAGUUGCGUGCACUGAACUUGACCGAGGGAUUCGCCGUGCUGCACUGGAAGCCCCCCCAGAAUCCUGUGGACACCUAUGACGUCCAGGUCACAGCCCCUGGGGCCCCGCCUCUGCAGGCGGAGACCCCAGGCAGCGCGGUGGACUACCCCCUGCAUGACCUUGUCCUCCACACCAACUACACCGCCACAGUGCGUGGCCUGCGGGGCCCCAACCUCACUUCCCCAGCCAGCAUCACCUUCACCACAGGGCUAGAGGCCCCUCGGGACUUGGAGGCCAAGGAAGUGACCCCCCGCACCGCCCUGCUCACUUGGACUGAGCCCCCAGUCCGGCCCGCAGGCUACCUGCUCAGCUUCCACACCCCUGGUGGACAGAACCAGGAGAUCCUGCUCCCAGGAGGGAUCACAUCUCACCAGCUCCUUGGCCUCUUUCCCUCCACCUCCUACAAUGCACGGCUCCAGGCCAUGUGGGGCCAGAGCCUCCUGCCGCCCGUGUCCACCUCUUUCACCACGGGUGGGCUGCGGAUCCCCUUCCCCAGGGACUGCGGGGAGGAGAUGCAGAACGGAGCCGGUGCCUCCAGGACCAGCACCAUCUUCCUCAACGGCAACCGCGAGCGGCCCCUGAACGUGUUUUGCGACAUGGAGACUGAUGGGGGCGGCUGGCUGGUGUUCCAGCGCCGCAUGGAUGGACAGACAGACUUCUGGAGGGACUGGGAGGACUAUGCCCAUGGUUUUGGGAACAUCUCUGGAGAGUUCUGGCUGGGCAAUGAGGCCCUGCACAGCCUGACACAGGCAGGUGACUACUCCAUGCGCGUGGACCUGCGGGCUGGGGACGAGGCUGUGUUCGCCCAGUACGACUCCUUCCACGUAGACUCGGCUGCGGAGUACUACCGCCUCCACUUGGAGGGCUACCACGGCACCGCAGGGGACUCCAUGAGCUACCACAGCGGCAGUGUCUUCUCUGCCCGUGAUCGGGACCCCAACAGCUUGCUCAUCUCCUGCGCUGUCUCCUACCGAGGGGCCUGGUGGUACAGGAACUGCCACUACGCCAACCUCAACGGGCUCUACGGGAGCACAGUGGACCAUCAGGGAGUGAGCUGGUACCACUGGAAGGGCUUCGAGUUCUCGGUGCCCUUCACGGAAAUGAAGCUGAGACCAAGAAACUUUCGCUCCCCAGCGGGGGGAGGCUGAGCUGCUGCCCACCUCUCUCGCACCCCAGUAUGACUGCCGAGCACUGAGGGGUCGCCCCGAGAGAAGAGCCAGGGUCCUUCACCACCCAGCCGCUGGAGGAAGCCUUCUCUGCCAGCGAUCUCGCAGCACUGUGUUUACAGGGGGGAGGGGAGGGGUUCGUACGGGAGCAAUAAAGGAGAAACUGAGGUACCCGGCU